GGUGGCGCAGAAUAGCACUCUUUGAUUCUUCGAAACCUGUUCCCAAGAUAUGACUGAGAGAGUCCAUCCCUGAAACUGGGGCAGAGUGAGAAUUGAGGCAAGGAGAAGCUAGUGGACCUGGAAUGCAAGGCCACCCUCACUGACCUGGGCUUUGCUGAGCCCCAGACGGGGCUUCUCCUACAGACAGCUGUCACCCAGGGAGAAAGGUCAGGGGUCCUCUGCUCUGAGUGGAGAAUUUGGUAUCUAAUCCCCCAGUUUACUUCAGCCCCCAGGCUGUCACCUGAAGUAGAUGAACAAAGAGGCAGUAAAAAGAGACGCUUCUUGAGAACAAUAAUGCGGAUUGGCGAAAGAACAGCACCUGGGGUCCCAGAGACAGCUGGGCUCAGAUUCCAGUCCUCUGCCUUCUCCUUGGGAGGUGACUGUGCAAGUAACCUGUGCAGCCUGAAUCUGGCCCCUUGAUUGUAAAAGGGUUGAACUGACCUGAGGAUGAAAUGCAAAUACAGCAAGAAAAGUACCUUGUCUAACAGGCACUCGGUGCACGUUCGUCUCCUUGCCUGGGCUCUCCUCUGGUUGGAUGGAAGCGAGAAUGAACAGCACUUUGGAGUUAGAGAGGACCUUCCUGUUCAGUGAAGGUCAAAAGGGGCAGGAAUUGGAGAGACGUCUACAAAGCUUCCAACACCAUGGCCCUGGGGGUGACCUCCUCGGUACCCUGCCUGCCCCUCCCCAACAUCCUACUCAUGGCCAGUGUCAAAUGGCACCAGGGGCAGAACCAGACAUGGAACAGACCAUCCAUAGCCCCCAACAUCUUCCUGAAGAGCCUUAGUCCUAAAGGAGACCUGCCUCAUUUUAACGAAGACAGGGUCAGAUUGGAUGCAAUAGGGUUGUCAGUGUGUGUCUUCCCUGGUGGCUUCAGGAUUCUCCCAUUGAGGUUUGUGGAGCUCCAGGUAUGUGACCACUAUCAACGCAUCCUGCAGUUGAGGACAGUCACUGAGAAGAUUUAUUACCUAAAGCUCCAUCCUGACCAUCCUGAGACUGUCUUCCACUUCUGGAUCCGACUGGUUCAAAUUCUGCAAAAGGGGCUGUCCAUCACCACCAAAGACCCUAGGAUUCUUGUCACGCACUGCCUGGUACCCAAGAACUGCAGCAGCCCCUCAGGAGAUUCGAAGUUAGUACAGAAGAAACUCCAAGCCUCCCAGCCCAGCGAGAGUCUCAUUCAGCUAAUGACCAAGGGGGAGAGUGAAGCCCUGUCUCAGAUUUUUGCCGACUUACACCAGCAGAACCAGUUGAGGAGCAGCAGAAAGGUGGAGACCAACAAGAACAGCUCAGGGAAAGAUUCUUCCCGUGAAGACAGCAUCCCUUGCACCUGUGACCUACGUUGGAGGGCUUCAUUCACGUACGGAGAGUGGGAAAGAGAGAACCCCUCCGGCCUGCAGCCCCUCUCACUACUCAGCACUCUGGCAGCCUCCACCGGGCCACAGCUGGCCCCACCCAUAGGAAAUUCUAUUUGAGCCACCCUUCCGCACUGGGGAGAAUCUAUGCAAGCCUCGUCAACACCACUUUGCAGCAUUCAGCUGCUGAGGGAUUAUCGGGAUGGAGAGUAGGAGAAAACUGCAACCAAGGAAGAAUAGAGUCAUCUCACGGUGACAGCAGAGCCUUUCCAGCUGUACAUAACCACGUCCUCGCCACUGCACCUCGGCAUAUGCCACCUCCAUGCCACUGCCAGAGCUGGCCUAGCAAGAUGUGCUCUCAGAAUGGCCGGGCCCAAGAGAUGAAGGAAAGGAGUGAAAGGGAAGUAGGACCAGAGAAGUGGAAGGAAGCAAAAUGGAGGUGAUGAGAAAGGUGGUGGGAGAAAGUCAGCAGAUGAGAGACACAAAGAGAAGUGGUAAUAGGAAACGGAAGAGACUUGGUAGACGAGAUAAGGAGGACAAGAGAAGGGACACACCCCUGAGAGAUGCUCACCAAGCUUCUAUUUAUCUAAUUUAAAACUUGAAAGUAAAGCCAUAAACAAAAAAAAGAAAUGUUUUCUUCCCUGCUCAGACCAUUCUGGACAAAUGUGAACUGCCAGACACCUUCCAUUUCCCUUUCUAUCUGUUUUUCUUGCUAGUUCCUGUCUUCUGAUUAAAGCUUCAUUCCUUCUU